GCUGUGCACCCAGAGAUAGUUGGGUGACAAAUCACCUCCAGGUUGGGGAUGCCUCAGACUUGUGAUGGGACUGGGCAGAUGCAUCUGGGAAGUAACUGCUGCAAGAACGGACAGACACUGCUGCAGAGAACUUGCCACGGUGUUUCAUGCUGUGGCUGGUGGUUCCAGGCUGCACGCUCCAUUCUAGGAAAGGGCUGGACCUUGGAGAGUGAGGCCCUGAGGCGAGACAUGGGCACCUGGCUCCUGGCCUGCAUCUGCAUCUGCACCUGUGUCUGCUUGGGAGUCUCUGUCACAGGGGAAGGACAAGGGCCAAGGUCUAGAACCUUCACCUGCCUCACCAACAACAUUCUCAGGAUCGAUUGCCACUGGUCUGCCCCAGAGCUGGGACAGGGCUCCAGCCCCUGGCUCCUCUUCACCAGCAACCAGGCUCCUGGCGGCACACAUAAGUGCAUCUUGCGGGGCAGUGAGUGCACCGUCGUGCUGCCACCUGAGGCAGUGCUCGUGCCAUCUGACAAUUUCACCAUCACUUUCCACCACUGCAUGUCUGGGAGGGAGCAGGUCAGCCUGGUGGACCCGGAGUACCUGCCCCGGAGACACGUUAAGCUGGACCCGCCCUCUGACUUGCAGAGCAACAUCAGUUCUGGCCACUGCAUCCUGACCUGGAGCAUCAGUCCUGCCUUGGAGCCAAUGACCACACUUCUCAGCUAUGAGCUGGCCUUCAAGAAGCAGGAAGAGGCCUGGGAGCAGGCCCAGCACAGGGAUCACAUUGUCGGGGUGACCUGGCUUAUACUUGAAGCCUUUGAGCUGGACCCUGGCUUUAUCCAUGAGGCCAGGCUGCGUGUCCAGAUGGCCACACUGGAGGAUGAUGUGGUAGAGGAGGAGCGUUAUACAGGCCAGUGGAGUGAGUGGAGCCAGCCUGUGUGCUUCCAGGCUCCCCAGAGACAAGGCCCUCUGAUCCCACCCUGGGGGUGGCCAGGCAACACCCUUGUUGCUGUGUCCAUCUUUCUCCUGCUGACUGGCCCGACCUACCUCCUGUUCAAGCUGUCGCCCAGGGUGAAGAGAAUCUUCUACCAGAACGUGCCCUCUCCAGCGAUGUUCUUCCAGCCCCUCUACAGUGUACACAAUGGGAACUUCCAGCUUUCUGCACCCACCAUGUGCCUCACCUCCUCCUUCUGCGAAGGUGUCUGUCCUGUGGCCAUGGGGAAGGGUCUGUGGUGUGUGUGCUGCCCUUGGGGCUCUCACUGCCUCUGGGCUCCUGCUCUGCCUGGUCCCCUGGUCUCCCCGGAUCACAUGAUGGCACCACAGCUGAGGAGUGGGCUCUGCACUUCCCCCCCUUCCACCCAUGUUGGGCUCCUACAGCCCAGGCACCAGUGAGCAACUUGGGGGUUGCAUCAGCCCCUCCCCUCCCUGCUGGGCUGUUGGUUCAUGCCCCCUGGGUGGGAGGAGGGGGAGAGGGAGAGCUCCAGUGAGUGGUCUCUGGUUUUUCCCCUCAGACUCCUCACUUUGGGCAAAGGACAAGAGGCAGUGAGGGCCCCUCCCUGGGGUCUGGGCCAAGCUGACCACUCUUCUCCAGAAUCUUCCCUCCCUGUCCCCUUCACACUGUGGCUCCAGCUUACUAUGCAGAAAAAUCCUUUUCUCUCUCAAUGAGGAGCGUAGUUUUCAAGAUUUUUGUCCAAAAAUAUAAUUUGAACCAUGAACCGGGCAUCUGGCUCUUGGCAGAGUCUCCCUCUUUCCCCAAGGUGGUAGAUGUGACUGUCAGGAGCCUGGGCAGCUGACGACAAGGCUGAGCAGGUCAGAUUGUGACUGUCCCCUGGACUGUCAUCCUGUUGCGGGCACCAGCUGUUCCCUAGAGAACUAGGACACCUGCCACGGGUUAUUUAGACCUGCGGGUGAGGAUCUGGUGCCAUAGGUUGGUCUCCAGGGAGCACUGCAGUGAUGGAGGGUGUUGUGUGUGUGAUGCAUGGGAUGGAGGCUCCUGGUCCCACCAAGGGAACAGCUUCCUUUUGGAGGCGGGGGCCUCCUGUGGCCCCACAGAAGGAUCCAGGUCUGCUGGCCAUAGCCGAGUGCUUUGAAAGUCACCAGUCCUGACAGCGAUUCGUGUGUGUGUCUGUGUGUGUGUGUGUGUGUGUUUAUGUGUCUGUGUGUGUUCGUGUGUGUGUCUGUGUGUGUGUUUGUGUGUGUAUGUCUGUGUGUGUGUGUUUAUGUGUGUGUGUCUGUGUGUGUUUAAGUCUGUGUGUGUUUGUGUGUGUGUGUCUCUGUGUGUGUGUCUGUAUCUGUGUGUGUUUGUGUCUGUGUGUGUUUGUGUGUGUGUCUGUGUGUGUUUGUGUGUGUGUGUCUGUGUGUGUGUUUAUGUGUCUGUGUAUGUUUGUGUGUGUGUUUGUGUGUGUGUGUUUGUGUUUAUGUGUGUAUGUCUGUGUGUGUCUGUGUGUCUGUGUGUGUAUGUGUCUGUGUGUGUUUAUGUGUCUGUGUGUGUUCGUGUGGUGUGUGUGUCUGUGUGUGUGUGUUUGUGUGUGUAUGUCUGUGUGUGUGUGUGUUUAUGUGUGUGUGUCUGUGUGUGUUUAUGUCUGUGUGUGUUUGUGUGUGUGUGUCUCGUGUGUGUGUGUCUGUGUGUAUCUGUGUGUGUUUGUGUGUGUGUGUGUCUCUGUGUGUGUGUGUGUUUGUGUAUGUUUGUGUGUGUGUGUGUGUGUGUUGGGAAUGCCCAGUCUCUGCAGCUGCUGAAAGGCCCUGAGGCACAUGCUGUCAGGAGCUGGCUCUGUCCUGGGCAGAUAUCACCAUCUGUACCUCGGUUCAGGCUGCCGUGGGCACCAGGCCCUGUGCUGGGGGAGUGCUGAGGAGCCUGAAGGGACUCAGGGUCCCGUGAUGAGGCUGGGCUGGCACAUGGAGGAAAGACAGAAUGUCCAAGACACAGGCGCUGCUUGGCCUCUGGGUGUGGACCUCAGGAGGGCUUCCUGGAGGAGGAGGGAUGCUGGGCUUGCCAGAAAGGAGGCAGCUGCUCCCAGGAUGAGUUCUGAACAUGCUACCUGAGCCCUUCCCUCCUCCCGUGCUCUGUUCCAGACUUGGAUGGGGGCCCACGGGGCCGGUGUGCUGUUGAGCCAGGACUGUGCUGGCACCCCACAGGGAGCCUUGGAGCCCUGCGUCCAGGAGGCCACUGCACUGCUCACUUGUGGCCCAGCGCGUCCUUGGAAAUCUGUGGCCCUGGAGGAGGAACAGGAGGGCCCUGGGACCAGGCUCCCGGGGAACCUGAGCUCAGAGGAUGUGCUGCCAGCAGGGUGUACGGAGUGGAGGGUACAGACGCUUGCCUAUCUGCCACAGGAGGACUGGGCCCCCACGUCCCUGACUAGGCCGGCUCCCCCAGACUCAGAGGGCAGCAGGAGCAGCAGCAGCAGCAGCAGCAGCAACAACAACAACUACUGUGCCUUGGGCUGCUAUGGGGGAUGGCACCUCUCAGCCCUCCCAGGAAACACACAGAGCUCUGGGCCCAUCCCAGCCCUGGCCUGUGGCCUUUCUUGUGACCAUCAGGGCCUGGAGACCCAGCAAGGAGUUGCCUGGGUGCUGGCUGGUCACUGCCAGAGGCCUGGGCUGCAUGAGGACCUCCAGGGCAUGUUGCUCCCUUCUGUCCUCAGCAAGGCUCGGUCCUGGACAUUCUAGGUCCCUGACUCGCCAGAUGCAUCAUGUCCAUUUUGGGAAAAUGGACUGAAGUUUCUGGAGCCCUUGUCUGAGACUGAACCUCCUGAGAAGGGGCCCCUAGCAGCGGUCAGAGGUCCUGUCUGGAUGGAGGCUGGAGGCUCCCCCCUCAACCCCUCUGCUCAGUGCCUGUGGGGAGCAGCCUCUACCCUCAGCAUCCUGGCCACAAGUUCUUCCUUCCAUUGUCCCUUUUCUUUAUCCCUGACCUCUCUGAGAAGUGGGGUGUGGUCUCUCAGCUGUUCUGCCCUCAUACCCUUAAAGGGCCAGCCUGGGCCCAGUGGACACAGGUAAGGCACCAUGACCACCUGGUGUGACCUCUCUGUGCCUUACUGAGGCACCUUUCUAGAGAUUAAAAGGGGCUUGAUGGCUGUUCCAAAGUGUUGAUGGCUGGGAGAAGGGGCCAGAGGAGGAGUGAGGGGUGGGGUUUGUCCAGCCCUGGGCUUUCCGGGCUCUAGAGAUAGCAUGGUGUAGGCUCAAUGACAGUUCUGGGGACAGCAAGUUGGAGGUUCAGGGGCAGCUUCAGGACAGCAGGAUGGAGGCUCAGGGACAAUUCCUGGGAGGCCAGUGCCCUCGUUCCUCCUUGUCCUCAUCCUCCCCCUUGCUCCAGGAAACUGAGAGCUGAGCCUGGAGCUUCCAGACAGUCAGUGCUGGGGGUGACCAUCCAGCAGUGAUGGUGGCCUGUGAAGGGUCCUGCUUCUGUCCUCAGCCUCUCAUGGGGUGGGCUUGUGGAGGAGCUGUGGUCUGGAGAGAGUGGCAGUUGGAGCAGAACGUGCCUGCGUUUGUUUCCUAGGGCUGUCGUAACAAAGUGCCACAAAAUGGUUAGCUUAGAACCACAGAGAUUUGUUGUCUCACAAUUCUGAAGUCCAGAAGUUGGAAAUAAAGAUGUUGGCAGUGUUCCCAACCACAUGUUCUUGGGCUCCCAUGAAACAGAAGUUGAUAUUAGGCCAAGGAAGCUUCCCAGACAAGACUUUAUUAAGUCUUAUGCCCCGAAAGUUUGGGCAGAAGAGAGACGGUGCAGGAGGAAGAAUUCUUGGCUGACUCCCCAAGGGGAAUGCAUUGUGGUGUCUUAAGGAGGGUGACAUACAUAAUUUAUGAGCUACAUGAGUGUCAUUGCACAUAUGGGGUGGAGCGAAGGGUGCUCAGACGCAUGCUAACACAUACGUUGCAUGAUCAGAAAAUGGCAGAUAAGCCCCUCCCUGGGUGAGGACUUUAGUAUUAUCAUAAGACCAGGGUCAUUCUCCUGGCCUUGUGCACAAGCAGGUGAUGGAGUCAACUCCCGUCAGUAAGACUUAUGGCGGGAUGCUGCUUAUCUUAGUUUAUUUCAGACAGUUGGCAAGGUCUGGCCAGCGAGUAUGGCACCUGGAGGGUGGUGCUGCAAGGUCUAGUGGUCAGCGGGCACGUAUGGAACAAUACGUUAGUGGGGGUGGGCCGAGUCCCAUUUAUACUCUCUCAGCAGGGCCAUGCUCCCUCUGAAGGCACUAGGGAAGGAUUAGUUUCAGGCCUCUCUUCAGCUUCUGUUAGUUUCUUGGCUUGUGACACCAAAGCUGUAAUCUUUCUUUUGUUUUGUUUUUGUGACGGAGUUUUGCUCUUGUUGCCCAGGCUGGAGUGCAAUGGCACAAUCUCGGCUCACUGCAACCUCCUCCUCCCAGGUUCAAGCAAUUCUUCUGCCUCAGCCUUUGGAGUAGCUGUGAUUACAGGCACCUGCUACCACGCCUGGCUAGUUUUUGUAUUUUUAGUAGAGACGGUGUUUCGCUAUGUUGGCCAGGCUGGUCUCAAACUCCUGAUAUCAAGUGAUCCGUCUGUCUCUGCCUCCCAAAGUGUUGGGAUUACAGGCAUGAGCCACCGUGCCUGGCCAAAGUUCCAGUCUUUACAGGGAUUUUUCCUUGUGUGCAUUUCUGUGUCCAAAUUUCCCCUUUUUAAAAUCACAAUAAUAGUGAAUUAAGGCUGGCCCUAACGAUUUAAUCUUAACUUGAUCAUCUGCAAAGACACUGUUUCCAUAUAAGGUCACAUUCACAGCUACUGGGGUUAGGACUUCAACCUAGAGGGCCUGACUUCUGGCCCAACACAUCAUGGCCCAUCCCAGCAUGCCCCAUCCCCUUCCUGGGUGCCCCAGGCAGAUCACAGGAGGGCCUGACUGCUGGGCUUUGGGCUGACAUUGGGAUCAUCUGCCUAGUUAGGGCUGUGACCAGACUGAGAUAGGAGGUGGGACCUGACUCCUGAGGCAGGGCUUGAACUCUGGACCAGAUUACAGACUAGCUGAAACAGGCAAAAGCACCCCUCCAUAAGACACACCCACUGGUGCCAAGUGAGUUUGCCGUUCUCAUGGUAACAGCUGGAAAUUACUGCCCCUUUCCAUGGCAAUGACCUGAAAGUUACCACCCCUUUUCUAGAAAUUUCUAAAUAACCUCCUCCUUAAUUUGUAUAUAGUUACAAGUGGGUAUAAAUAUGUGUGCAGAACUGCCUCUGAGCUGCUACUCUGGGCUGACUGCCUAUGGGGCAUCCCUGCUCCAUAAGGAGCAGUACCUCUGCUGCCACUGUGCACAGCUGCUUAAAUAAAAGUUGCUCUCUAAUACCA